AUUGCUCCGGGUCCAUUACCGAGAAUCCCCAAACCUAGUCCGCCGCUGCGUGGCCCCUCUCCCCAUGCAAAGCAGACCCCCGAAGAAGCCAUGCCAGGCUGAGGGACAGACGCCGGGGCUCGAAGCUCCGGGCAGAUUCAGAAAGAGGCGUCGCUGCAGAAAGGACGCAUCACAGUUUUCAGAUCUUAAUGUGGCCGAGGUUUUACAACUCCCGACCCGGCGCAGAAAGGAAAUCCCACCAUGUUCCCCGGAGUCGAGAAAACGGUGAACAGCUUUCGGCCUGCGCUCGACCUCUGCGUCUGCGUCUCUCUCGCCUCGGCUUCCCUUAUUUUUUAAACCACCACCACACUCCUUCCCCCGCCACUUCCUUCCCCCACCCCCUUCCUCCGUUGCACCAGCAGCAGAGUCGCACGCAGCAAAUACUCCUUCAAGAAUUUUACCUACCUACAGUUCAAGCAGUUACUGGGAUGUCCUGACUAAUCGAAGAUGCUGCCGCGCGCGUGGGUCGCUCUGCGCAAGGGCCUCUUCGAAAACCCGACUAGGCGCAACUCAGCGUUCAGCAGGGCCGGGAGCGCCAGGUCGUCCCCGGGGCCCGGGCCCCAUGACUCCUGCCCCAAAGCCCACUCCACCCGACCUCCCUUUCCUGAGGCUGUUCCCAGUUGCUGCUUUGGGUCGCUCCGGAGCUCAAGAACUCGGGUUGCCUGCCGCCCCACUCUCCACGCACAUACUUGGUUUUCUUCUUAGGGGCAUUGGCAGGUAGACUUUGAGGAAGAAAAGUAAAGGAUCGAACAGCUCAGCCCUCCCUCCCGACCGUGGAUGCCCGGAGUCGACCAACACCUCAGGUCCGGGUGCGGAGGCCGCGGGCGCCCCUGCGCGACCGUCCGCGCCCGGCAAGAGCCGCGCGGCUUUCGCCUUUGCUGGUCCCGCGCCACCGCUGGGGCGGGCUGCGAAAGGGUUGGGAAGAGCAAAGGGUUUUUUUGUUUUGUUUUGAGACGCAGAAGCCCUUUAAAAAGCCCGGCGAGGAGAGGUCCAGAAGUAGAGAAAGCAGACGGAGGCAAGCUGUGCCCGCGGGGCAAAGGGACAGUAGAAGGGGCGGGCGCCCGGGUUCCCCGGAAAACCCUCGGCCCCAAGGAAUCUCCUGGGGCGGGAGAGCGCGGUUCUAAAACCGAGAGGAUAGGAAGGGGAAGGGGGAGUUGUGUUUCAAUUUCGGAUUCACCAGGAUUCAUCUCUAGUCACAUUUUUCUUCUCAAAUUUUUAAAUCGAAAAGAUAAAAGCCAAAAGAACUUUCAUCCCCAGAGCUUUUUAUUGGGGGAAAGGAAUGUAACUCGGGGUGGUUGUCCUUCACUUCCCUACUCGAAUCUUCUCCUAAUGCCGAAAUGUGUUUACAGGUAGCCUCAGUUUACCAAGUAUGUAUCUUUUGGGGGUUUAACCUCUCACAAAGCCUUCAACUCACAAACCGCGAUCCUUGGAAACCAUCCUCCAAAGCAGUGCUUGGAGGCCUCUAAGGCCCCCGGACCAACUCCCGCUGGAAGAAGCCUGCAGGGACUCGGGAAUCACGGGAACCUUUCCCGUCGGUUCCGGGCCUGGAGGGCCAGGAAGAGCCGCGCGUCCGCCUUUCGUCCCGCCAGGAACUCCCCAUAGGACACGACACCGCAGGAACAAGCGUCCUGGGAGCCCCUGGGAUCUUGGCUGUCGUCUCUAGGGACCCUACACCGUGAAAUGAUAGAGGCGAGGUUCCUUGGGUUCCGCAAGUCGACGAAAAUAGCUCGUGGAGAAGGCGCGUCCUGCAACUGCAGUUCGCAAGCUCUCAGGGCGCCCCGCCAGCUGGGGGCCAGAUUGGGUGACACUCCCCUCGACGCAGCCUCCGGAGCGGCGCGCACUCUCCAGAGGCCAGCAGGACUGCGCUCUCUACCGCAGAACCUGCUCCAGCUAGGUGUUCUCUCCCCAUCUCGCCGUCGCUCUGCCCCCUCACUCUCUCUGGACCUCAGAGCCGGUUCUCUCCUUCCUCCUCCCGCGCUUUCCGUCCGGGGAUCGCAACCUCCAGCCCGUGGGCAACGCGUUCAGCCCAAGACCCCACAGUUUUUCCCAACGACCCCCCUACCAAGGGCUUCUCUUGUUUCUGCUCUCCUGCCCCGCACUUCCCAAAGUGUGUGGGAACAGUGUAACCUGAACAAGAACGUAGUGUCUAUAGGAUGAGUGACACUUGGAAGCAGAGGCAGAGUGCUACAUGGACACCUGACUGUACCAAAUGGUUAUUGUGUUUUCUCAAUCAGACGCCAAUUGCGGAAUACCAGCUGAUAUUCUACCCUCAACUCAUGCUAAAAGCUUUCUAGUCUUUCUCAAGGAAACCUGUCCAAAGGGAUAUGUGAUCCCAGGAAUUAUUAUUGUAUAAGUAAUACUUGGAUGUUUUUACUAAUAGUUCACACAUUUCACAGCCCUUUGGUGGAGAGCCUUUUUCGUUAAUGUUCUGUUCAAGAAUAAUUGCAUAGUAUUUAUAAUCCUCUCAGGGAUUAAGUAUAGAUGUAAUACACAACUCAAAGAUGCUUGUUGAUGUUCACUUUGUAAAAAUUCAUCAAGUUGUAUACUUGAUAUUUGUGCACUUUCUGUGUUACAUAUUUUUUAAUUAAAUACUUAUAGAAACUA